AUAGAGGGACAGAUGGAAUAAGACAGAAAUCAAGAGGAGGACUAUGCUCCAAGAAUAAGCUCUCAAACCUAUCUUCAGGGCCCAAGGAGGAGCUCUGUGUACUUGGAAUAAGAGCUUGCCCAGAGUAGGGAUUAUGACCACCCUUUCCUGGCCUCCAGCCUUCCACAGAUAAGGAAGGGCUUGUGGGCCACAUUAAGGGCCAUAUGGGGGCCUGCAUGCCAAAGUCACAACCAGGCUUCUCAGGCCUUGUCACCUCCAUAAACAGAGGUCAAGAGGAUGCCCCACAUACGUACCCUCCCUGCCCUCACAAAAAGCCACAGCUUCACCACCAGGUGAAGCCUUGAACCCACCAGGAGUAACUGCAUUAUACGGUUUACCUAUCUAUGAGCAGUCAUGCCAAGCAGAAAGCCCCAUAAGGAUCUGCACAGUCCCUGUUUCUGCCCCUGCCUCCCACUGCCCUCAACACCUGAAACACAUCACCUAUGCCUCUAAAGCUUGCUGUCCAUCAACAGCAAAAUCCCUUAUAUCUUUGAUCUCUUCUCUAAAUGCAGCUUUCAACAUGGAAAAGGGUCCUGAGGCACCUGAAGAGAGAGGAAGCUGUGGGACAGGUCCAGCCAGAGCCCAGGCCAGAGGGGCAGAAGCUGGAGUCCUGGAGCACAGACGCAGGUUGUCAGCAAACACUGAGGCCUGUUGUUUCUCCUCCUCUACCGGCUCUGAUGCGGUCAAGGUCCAGAGAGCUGAGUAGUUGGCAAGCGGACCACCAGCAACAGACAACAUCUUCAUUCGGCUCUCCCUGAAGCUGUACUGCCUCGCUGAGAGGAUGAAGGUCUCCGAGGCUGCCCUGUCUCUCCUUGUCCUCAUCCUUAUCAUUACUUCGGCUUCUCGCAGCCAGCCAAAAGUUCCUGAGUGGGUGAACACCCCAUCCACCUGCUGCCUGAAGUAUUAUGAGAAAGUGUUGCCAAGGAGACUAGUGGUGGGAUACAGAAAGGCCCUCAACUGUCACCUGCCAGCAAUCAUCUUCGUCACCAAGAGGAACCGAGAAGUCUGCACCAACCCCAAUGACGACUGGGUCCAAGAGUACAUCAAGGAUCCCAACCUACCUUUGCUGCCUACCAGGAACUUGUCCACGGUUAAAAUUAUUACAGCAAAGAAUGGUCAACCCCAGCUCCUCAACUCCCAGUGAUGACCAGGCUUUAGUGGAAGCCCUUGUUUACAGAAGAGAGGGGUAAACCUAUGAAAACAGGGGAAGCCUUAUUAGGCUGAAACUAGCCAGUCACAUUGAGAGAAGCAGAACAAUGAUCAAAAUAAAGGAGAAGUAUUUCGAAUAUUUUCUCAAUCUUAGGAGGAAAUACCAAAGUUAAGGGACGUGGGCAGAGGUACGCUCUUUUAUUUUUAUAUUUAUAUUUUUAUUUUUUUGAGAUAGGGUCUUACUCUGUCACCCAGGCUGGAGUGCAGUGGUGUGAUCUUGGCUCACUUGAUCUUGGCUCACUGUAACCUCCACCUCCCAGGCUCAAGUGAUCCUCCCACCCCAGCCUCCUGAGUAGCUGGGACUACAGGCUUGCGCCACCACACCUGGCUAAUUUUUGUAUUUUUGGUAGAGACGGGAUUCUACCAUGUUGCCCAGGCUGGUCUCAAACUCGUGUGCCCAAGCAAUCCACCUGCCUCAGCCUUCCAAAAGUGCUGGGAUUACAGGCGUGAGCCACCACAUCCGGCCAGUGCACUCUUAAUACACAGAAAAAUAUAUUUCACAUCCUUCUCCUGCUCUCUUUCAAUUCCUCACUUCACACCAGUACACAAGCCAUUCUAAAUACUUAGCCAGUUUCCAGCCUUCCAGAUGAUCUUUGCCCUCUGGGUCUUGACCCAUUAAGAGCCCCAUAGAACUCUUGAUUUUUCCUGUCCAUCUUUAUGGAUUUUUCUGGAUCUAUAUUUUCUUCAAUUAUUCUUUCAUUUUAUAAUGCAACUUUUUCAUAGGAAGUCCGGAUGGGAAUAUUCACAUUAAUCAUUUUUGCAGAGACUUUGCUAGAUCCUCUCAUAUUUUGUCUUCCUCAGGGUGGCAGGGGUACAGAGAGUGCCUGAUUGGAAAAAAAAAAAAAAGAGAGAGAGAGAGAAGAAGAAGAAGAAGAGACACAAAUCUCUACCUCCCAUGUUAAGCUUUGCAGGACAGGGAAAGAAAGGGUAUGAGACACGGCUAGGGGUAAACUCUUAGUCCAAAACCCAAGCAUGCAAUAAAUAAAACUCCCUUAUUUGACA